GUGCUGGGAUUACAGGCAUGAGUCACCACGCCCGGGCGUCUUUGUAACUUUUAAAAUGGAGAACUUGGCCUUUUUUUAUUCUCCAAUUUGGGAGGGGAUUUAGGAGUGUGAUUUGUAUUUAGGUGCACAGCUUAUACUUAAAAGUAUGUCUUAGCUUACAUUCUUCUCUCACAAACUUUGUUAAAAUUAAUGCUUGUUUAUUUUUAAAAUCAAAGUGAAACAUGGAUAGAGUCACACAGUCAAACAGGAUUAAAGAUGUCACAGGGGUCAGCAGUAAUCUUCUGUGCUCCCCUCUGCCCCUAAAACCUUUAAAGUCUUUAGAUUUUUUAAGUAAUGUGCUCAUUCUUCUAUUUCCUAAUUUAUUAAUUCUGGAUAUUGUCCCUGCUGUGGUAGAUAAGGACUUAGCUUUCUGGCACCUCCUCCCACUUCUCCAGUCUCAUUCCUCUCAUCUCAUUCAGAUCUCAGUUUUUGGUGGUUGUACUGGUCACUGUUUACAUUAUGACUCAGAAGGUCUUGCCUGGUUCACUCUUUUUUUUUUUUUUUGUUAUUGAGAUGGAGUCUCCCUCUUGUUGCCCAGGCUGGAGUGCAGUGGCGAGAUCUCGGCUCACUGCAACCUCUGCCUCCCAGGUUCAAGUGAUUCUCCUGCUUUAGCCUCCCAAAGAGCUGGGAUUACAGGCAUGUGCCGCCACGCCCGGCUAGUUUUGUAUUUUUAAAAGAGACAGGGUUUCACCAUGUUGGCCAGGCUGGUCUUGAACUCCUGAUUUCAGGUGAUCUGCCCGCCUCAGUCUCCCAAAGUGCUGGGAUUAUAGGCGUGAGCCACUGCAUCCAGCUGGGUCACUCUUAAGCCAGGUAGUGCCGUGCGAUUAUUUUCUUUCUUGUACAAUAUUUUGUUUUUCUUAGAUUUUAACAAUAAUCUCAGUUUUUGUUUGCCUAGUUUUCUGUGUAGGUAUCUCUGAUUUUUUCCAAAUAGUCCAUUACAAAUGUUAGGCAUGUAUUUAUUUUCCAAUAAUUCAAAUGUUUUCAAUAAUUUGUCACUUUUUAAAAAAAAAAUUGACUCUCCCCUCCUGGUCUGAUCUGGUUUGGUUGCUUGUCUUGGGACUUCCCUUUGCUACUUUCCCUGUUUCAAAUUCCCUUCUCUUCCUCUCUCUGGCUUUACUCCCUCACUUUGCUUGAGUAUAUCCUCCAGUAGCCUCCUGGUGCCUCCUUGUGCUGAGCCUUUCUGCAGCUUGUGGUGGGGAAUCAGUUCUUGUCAUGGGUAUACCCCUUGCAGGCCUCUGUUAUCAGUGUUAAGUCAAGAUACCUUCUUUGCAUCCAGUGUUUGUCUUCCAGUGUCUUGUGGAAAUGUCUUGUCUAUUGAUGUCUUUGCUCUCAUUUCCUUUGACUGUUUUUACUGUCACUUUAAUAGUGUUUCAGGAUGGAGAGGAGGUGGUGGUGAUGAUGGUAAUAAUAUUACUAAUAGCGACUAGCAAAUAUUGAGUCUUGCUAUGGGACAGGCACUGUUAUAAGGGUUUUGUUUAACUCAUUCAAUCCUCAAAAUAACUAUAUGAAGUAGGUACUAUUAUUAGUGCCAGAGGUGUUAAGUAACUUGCCCAAGGUCACACAGCAAAUAAUUGCCUGGGCUAGAAUUCAGACCCAGGCAGCCUGGGUCCAGAGUCUGUGCUCUUGGCCACCAUGCUGUGUGGCCUUUCUUAAGGUACAAGGGAUAGUUGGAGUCCCUCAACACAUUUUUUUGGGGGGGGGGUGGUAAUGAAUGAAUCUAUUUUAGUAUGGACAAUUACAAAUAAUCUUUCCAGCAAGAUCACAUCUUGCUGUGAAACAUGGAUGGAGCUGGAGGCCAUUAUCCUUAGCAAGCUAACGCAGGAACAGGAAGCCAAAUACUGCAUGUUCUCACAAGUGGAAGCUAAAUGAUGGGGACUCAUGGACAUAUAGAGGUGAACAAUAGACUCUGGGAUCUACUGGAGGGUGGAGGGUGGGAGAAGGGAGAGGAUCAGGAAAAAUAACUAAUGGAUAGGGUACUAGGGCUUAGUACAUGGGUAAUGAAAUAUCUACAACAAACCCCCAUGACAUGAAUUUACCUAUAUAACAAACCUGCACAUGUACCCCUGAACCUAAAAGUUAAAACAAAAAACUUUUCAUGUAUUUUGUAAGUAACAUGUAUAUUAAAUAUAAUUAAUACAUUUUUGUGCACAUGUCUCAUUUUCUUAGGAUAAGUGAAAUUGCCAGGUGAAUGUUGUUCAUUCAUUUUAAGGCUUUUGAAAUGGCUCAGUUUACCUCCAGAUUGUACCAUUCCCAACAGACUUACUUUUAACUUAUAUUUUAAAGUUGUUGCUACAUUUAACAUAUUACAAUUUUUAGUUUUUCUUUCUCUAAACCUCUUAAAUGAGCAUUCAUUUGUUCCCCUACUCAUAGCUCCUAAUGUUUUCCCAGAAUUAUUGUUGCAGUGGUGAGGGUGGGGGAGAGAACGAAGAAGGCAAGGUUAUGCAUGUUUAUGAGAAUCCUCACCAGGUCUCUCUAUUCUGUCUCUCCAUCUCUGUUUCUGCUGUUGGCCCCCUCCAUAGACACUUACCCCUUCUCUCCUGGGUUCUUGGGGUUUGCUGCAGGGCACUCCAUCCUGGACAUUCUUGCCAGACUGAUUCCCUAAAUCAUUACUCCCAAUAAUCCCCUCCUCUGAAUGCCUGGAUGGCUCCCUGCUCUCUACAGAAUAAAGGCUAAGCCAUAUGCUUAGGCUUAGGUUUGAGAUUUUUAUCAACCUGCUUUAAACUCUUCGCUUCCUCUUCUUCCAUACACAGCUCCUUGACUUACUAGAUUGGUCAAGACUCUUGGUUGAAAGUGACUGAAACUCAAACUGGCUCAGAAACUAAUGGUACAGUCCACAGACAGAGUGAGCUUGCAGGUGUGGCUGGCUCCAGGGGCCAAAUUGCUAUUGUCAGAACUCUUUCCAGCUCUUGGCCUUCCUCUCUGGCUUGGCUCACUCUCAGGCAAGCCCCUCCUUGGUGACCCCUGGCACUACCAAGCCCACAUCCCCCCAGCUCCAGGUCAAGAAGAACAGAGGAGCUUUGUUUCUCCACAUUCCACUGGAGUCUCAGGACUGAAUCUCAUCAGAAUGACUUGAGUCAUGUGUUUGGUCUUGAACCAUUAUGAUGAAGAGAGACAGGAUUCCGGGCAGGCAAAGACAGCACAGGGAUUCUUUUCCCUUGACAUCUUCUUUCUUGCCACCUGGCAUUUGCUCCUGCUGGUGUUCUGCCAGCGUGCAGUUUUCCUUCCUCUCUGCUUCUUGAAAUCCUACCCACCCUCCAUGGCCAACUUGUGGUGAGUCCUCUGCUCACCCUCUCAGCCUGAAAUGCUUUCUCCUCUUUCUUCUCCUGGGGUUCACAGGAGAAGAAUUGCCUUGUUUCUUGUAUAUACACUGUCCAUUGUGUCAAGGAGUAUGGACAGUGUAUGAGGCAUUCAGGGAGAAGGAGCGUUCAGAAUGAGGCUGUAGGGAAGUUCACUGUUGCAUCGCUGCUGAGAAGGGUGUUGAGAGGCCUCAGUGUUGUCCCUGAUGAAGAAGUCAUUGAAAUGUACGAGGGGUCCCACGUGCCCUUGGAGCAGAUGAGUGACUUUUACGGAAAGAGCUCUCAUGGAAACACGAUGAAGCAGUUCAUGGACAUCUUCUCCCUGCCCGAGAUGACCCUCCUGUCCUGCGUGAAUGAAUACUUCCUCAAGAACAACAUCGACUAUGAGCCUGUGCAUCUGUACAAAGAUGUCAAGGAUUCAAUUCGAGACGUCCACAUCAAAGGAAUAAUGUACAGAGCAAUUGAAGCAGACAUUGAAAAGUACAUCUGCUAUGCUGAGCAGACCCGCGCAGUGUUGGCCAAACUGGCUGAUCAUGGCAAGAAGAUGUUUCUCAUCACCAAUAGCCCCAGUAGCUUUGUGGACAAAGGGAUGAGUUAUAUCGUUGGGAAAGACUGGAGGGACCUGUUCGAUGUGGUCAUUGUUCAGGCUGAGAAGCCAAACUUCUUUAAUGAUAAGCGGAGGCCUUUCCGAAAGAUGAAUGAGAAAGGUGUCUUACUCUGGGAUAAAAUCCAUAAGUUGCAGAAAGGCCAGAUAUACAAGCAGGGUAAUUUAUAUGAAUUUUUGAAGCUUACUGGAUGGAGAGGAUCCAGAGUGUUGUAUUUUGGUGACCAUAUAUACAGUGACCUGGCGGAUUUGACCCUAAAGCAUGGCUGGAGGACUGGUGCAAUCAUCCCAGAGUUGAGAUCUGAGCUCAAAAUCAUGAACACGGAGCAAUACAUUCAAACCAUGACCUGGCUGCAGACCUUGACUGGCUUAUUGGAACAGAUGCAGGUUCACAGAGAUGCUGAGUCACAGCUGGUUUUGCAGGAGUGGAAAAAGGAAAGGAAGGAGAUGCGAGAAAUGACCAAGAGUUUCUUCAAUGCCCAGUUUGGAAGCCUGUUCCGCACAGACCAGAACCCAACCUACUUCCUAAGGCGCCUGUCGCGCUUCGCUGACAUCUACAUGGCGUCUCUGAGCUGCCUCCUGAACUAUGACGUCAGCCACACUUUCUACCCCCGGAGGACUCCACUGCAGCACGAACUGCCCGCCUGGUCAGAAAGGCCCCCCACCUUCGGAACCCCUCUCCUGCAGGAGGCCCAGGCCAAGUAGCCAAGGGCAAAAACUAGAAACUGUAACUGCCCCUGAUUGGGCAGGCAUGAUGGGGUUGACUUCAUGUGGGUCUGAGUGUUGCUUUUGGAAAAGAUACAGAUAAGCCUUUUGAUAUUUAUUUUGUACCUUACGGAGAAUAAUUCUCCCAAUGGUUAAGACAGGAGCUAGCAGCCCACCCCUCCAGCCUUUCCCCCCAUGCAGGGCUGAAAGGCAAGCUUCACAUUGGAACUCUGAUUUUGCCUUUUUGUUUACUGAGGUCCUGGAACAUCAGGUUUCCUGGGAUAGGUGAGACCACUUGAUGCCAUGUCUGUAUUCUAGCAGGUCAAGCUUGAAACGGUUCUUGACUCCUCCAUGGAACAUUUCCUGAACAUUUACGGGCUAUGCAUUGGGAACUGCAGGGGCACAGUGAUGGGCAAAGAUUAGCUGCUUCCAGAAGGCUGAUUUCGUGGGCUCCACAAUGGUAAAACGCUGCUGUGAGUGGCAGAGAGGUUCCCCAGGUGAUGGCCAGUUCCCAAAUCAUUUGGUACUAAGGCUUUGACAUUCUGGCACAUCACAUCAAAUAGAACACAGCCUCCCUGGAAGGACUUAAGUGAGAAAGAACAAGAGAAGCUGCAACUCCUGGACCCUUUUGUCCUCAGUGUGUGGUUCCUGCGUCCUUCCCCAGCAUGGAGGAGGGCAGGAGAGAGGAGAUGAGAGCUCUGGUCAAAACCUGCCAGCUAGUGGAACAGCCUUCUGUAGAGCCUUCUGCAAGAAACGAGUGGGUUUGAAGAACCAAAACAUUUGUGGUAGGUCUCCCAGGAGCUUGUUAAACCUGGAAACACCACCUGAGUUGGUUUCAUCUGCUCAUUGGAAGAAAGAAAAUGAACCAGGAAAAAGCAUCUUUGUCAUGAAAUGCUAUGCCAUGCCACCCACCCAGUUGAAUUGGAAUCCUGUUAAAACAUGAGAUUUACCAGAAACAGUCCUUUGUCUAGAUGGAAACAAACAAGAUCCUGGCUUCUCUCUAAUGAGUUACCAACUGAGAGGUGCUUGGAUUGGCCAGGGGAGGAGGAAGAUGGCCACCACAACUUAGCCAUGUCCAGCCUUCUCUUAGAUUUCACUCCUGUGAUGUUUGUGCGACUAUUUGGGAGUUUGUGUAGUUUGUUUUUUUUUUUUUUGUUUUGUUUUGUUUUUUUUUAGAUGUCUAAGAUGGGAAAGGGCGAAGGACAUUGAAGCUAAGGAAUAGAUAUGACCUAGCUAACCAAGCUUUUCUCAUUUCCUUCUGUUUUGUUUUGUUGAGAUGGAGUUUUGCUCUUAUUGCCCAGGCUGGAGUGCAGUGGCACAAUCUCAGCUCACUGCAACCUCUGCCUCCCGGGUUCAAGCGAUUCUCCUGCCUCAGCCUCCCAAGUAGCUGGGAUUACAGGCAUGCACUACCACACCCAGCUAAUUUUGUAUUUCUAGUAGAGAUGGGGUUUCUCCAUGUUGGUCAGGCUGGUCUCGAACUCCCGACCUCAGAUAAUCUGCCCGCCUUGGCCUCCCAAAUUGCUGGGAUUACAGGUGUGAGCCACCGCACCUGGCCUGCUUUUUUCAUUUCUUUCUAGGGGCAAUGCAAGUGGCAUGUAUUCCUUUUGUUGGAGGGAAGAAUCCUUAAUUGCACCUGCAUUUGUAGUAUCCUUCAAUGUAAAGUGCAUAUUUACUGCACUCUCUGAGUGCUAUGGGAAUGUCUGCUGUUAUUAGUUAUGGGGCUGCUAAUACUGUUUUAAUUGCAUAUGCUAUAUCAAUACUUCUGUUCAGAUUAGCCUAAUCUAGUAUUGCUAAAACUCAUUUUAAGCUUUUGCGGUAACUUGUAUAUAUUCUUAAAUCUAAAGGAUGGCAGGAACAUGAGGGGAGCUUGUGGAGAGUGCUUGCUUAUUCAACAUUUUUAUUGUGAUAAAUGUAUGUAACCAUCUAUUGAUGAAAUCCAAGUCUGGCAUUCCAUGGGCUCCUUGCCAGAUGGCAGAAACUUAAUGAGUUAUAUAGCAUCCUUUGUAAUGCUGCUUGUUAUAGUUGGAAUGUACUUGUGAUAUUUGGCUGUAUUUAACUAUAAUGGUGAAGGUGACCCUUUAGAUCCAAUAAGGCUUCUCCCCAUCUUCUACAUUUUGUUAUGAACACAGUAAGGCACAGUAGUAUGUUCUUUUUUUGGAACAGGGUAGGCAUUUUGUUUAUUGUUUGCUUGCUUCUAGGUGUUUUCGCCAUCAGGGUGUAUUGGAGGCUGACACUUAAUGGGUGUGUGUUGCGCCCAGAACUGCUCGGUGUCGGGGUUCUAAAAGAAUGCGCUGGUGUUCUUGGCUUCAAGUUUCUGCUUUGGAGAAGCAGAUUCAGGAAGUAGGUGUUGCUUAAAAAUAAUUCUUGGUUUUUAUCUAAUCAGAUAUUCAUUGAUUACCUACCAGGUGCCAGUUAUAGGGUGUUUUGUUUACUCAAGAAUGAAGUAGAACUAUUUUUAAAACCUGUUUCCAUGAGUGUUCACGUUAGGUGACCUAAGCUUUGAAGGAGAAAAACAUUUUUGGGUAUGAAUAAUGAGUUUUGUAAUCAAUUCCCAGUUAGAAGAAUUUCAGUCUCUGGGCCAUUGAGCUUGGCAGUGUUGAGAUCUCCCAUGUGACAGAAGCCUGACAUCUGGGCCACCAAGGCUCACUGACUGUGUACCUUGCAGACUGUAGACCCAUGUCGUGGCGGUAACGGGGCCGAACACAGUCAUUCCCAUGUGAACGAUGGAGGCACAUCCCACUUUAUUAUUAAUCCUUGUAUAUACUCAGUCAGGACAGAUUUUAACUUGUCGCUGUCAUGACUUUUUUUUUUUUUUUUUGAGGCAAGGUCUCGCUCUGUUGCCCAUUCUGGAGUGCAGUGGUGUGAUCUCGGCUCACUGCAACCUCUUGCCUCCCAGGUUCAAGCAAUUUUCGUGCCUCAGCCUCCCGAGUAGCUGGGACUACUGGUACAUGCCACCAGGCCUGGCCAAGUUUUGUAGUUUUAAUAGAGAUGGGGUUUCACCAUGUUGGCCAGGCUGGUCUCAAACUCCUAGCCUCAAGUGUUCUGCCCACCUCAGCCUUCCAAAGUGCUGGGAUUCUGGGUGUGAGCCACUGUCAUGCCUGGCCUCGUCAUGACUCUUUUCUCUUUUUUUUUUUUUUUUUUUUUGAGAUUUAGUUUUGCUCUUUUUGCCCAGGCCGGAGUGCAAUGGCACGAUCUUGGCUCACUCCAACCUCCGCCUCCUGGGUUCAAGUGAUUCUCCUGCCUCAGCCUCCCGAGUAGCUGGGAUUACAGGUGCCCACCACCACAUCCAGCUAAUUUUUUUGUAUUUUUAGUAGAGACGGGGUUUCACCAUGUUGGCCAGGCUGGUCUCGAACUCCUGACCUUGGGUAAUCCACCUGCCUUGGCCUCCCAAGGUGCUGGGAUUACAGGCAUGAGCCACCGUGCCCAGCCUAUCAUGACUCAACUGGGAUCUGGCACACUGCACUGGGUGUUUUGUUCUCUGAUGUGCACAUUGAUGAAUGCAUAUUGGUACAAGGGAAAUGAAUCUGUUUUCAGCCAUUUAAAAAAUUGUGUUGUAAAGCAAACAAAAAUAGCUUGAACAUUUAAAAAUUACUGUUUAAUAUUGUUUGACUGAUUUUCUAAGAAUUAUGUGAACAAUGAUGAGUCCAGGGCAGCAGCCAUCACAAAUAUGACAGUCCAGCAAGGCCCAUGGAGGUCCCUUUGGAAGGGACUUGCACAGCUGAUUUUCUUUUUCCAGUGUUGUUUUUACGGGUGAAACGUGGCUUUUGAAAUACUUUAGUUGUUUGGCUUAGAGCUCCCACUUUCCCCCUAACAUAGUGCCUGUCUGUUUUUUAAAACAUUUUACCCUUCGGCACUAUUUUCUGCUAUUCCCAUUAAUAUUAUGUAACAUAAACCACUUGCUACUGAUUUGGGCAUAUUACAGACUACAAUUACUAGUUGCUUUGAAUGCAUUGGCACUCUUAAUUAUUGCAAAGGAGAAUUGAAAAGUAGUCUUGUGGUCCUAGUUAAUUUAGCUUUGGGCAAACUAAGUGGCUUUUCUUCUGUCCUCUUCUCAAAAGGCCUUUUAAGCAGCAGAGACUGGGCUAAAUACUGGAACUGAAUUCCACUUUUCUGCCUGCUCAUUUGCUGCCAAAGACCACUUGGGGCUCCUUGUCUAGAAUGCUCUAAGACGAAAUUUGGCCAGACACAGGGUUCCUUGAUUGUUCUGUUCAACUAAUAGAGAACCUACAUUUUGCCUUCUUAAUAUCGACUUUCUUUUGUACCAGGUUUUUCUUUCUUUCUUUUUUGCCUUAGGAGCUUAGCUCAAAGUUCAGCUAACCUUUGACACUACUAGUGUCAUUUAGUAACAGUAAUCUUUGACACUACUAGUGUCAUUUAGGAGCUUAGCUCAAAGUUCAGCUAACCUUUGACACUGCUAGUGCGUUCAAGAAAGGGUAGGGAAUGAAGUACCCUUAAUGCAGGGUCAGCAAACUUUUCCUGUAAAAGGCCAGAUAGGAAGUAUUUUUGGCUUUUUGGGCUGUUUGCUUUUGCUACUACUACUGUGGGAAUGACCAUGGUCAUGGCUGUGUUCCAGCACAACUUGAUUUACCAAGACAAGCUGUGGGCUGUAUUUGGUCCUCAGGCUGUGGCUUGCUAGCCCCUGCUCUAAUGGAUUGUGUUGGCGGCAAUGGCAAGAUUCCCUUGCUGAGAACAUGCAGAUGAAUAACCUUAUAGCUGGGAUGCAGAGAGGAGAAAGUUCUGUAGGUAAUAAGUGCACUGUAUUCCCUCUGAGCUACUUCCUGGGCAUAGUUACAUGUAUGGCCAGUGUGUGUACUUGAGCCAUCAGGCUCAGACACUUGUUGAAUAUACCUCUCAUUGCAUUAGUUUGUAAUUGUGCUAGUGCUGGGUGCUGAGCUCAGCUGCCCGGAUGACCUUUCCAGACUGAAGGACAUACUCCCCUAACAGCUGGGAGUGCUGCUGGCUGGCCAUUUACUUCCAGCCCUUAUGAGGAGUUUCCCCUGCUGAAGAGCCCUGCCUGCCCCAGAUCAUACCCCCUUCCUGCCUGUAACCCUUACCGGCUCCAUAUGGGGUACAAAGGGCUGGCCUCCUCACCCCAACUUGGGAAACCCUCUGGGGCCAUCCCAGCUCCAGAGCCCCUUGUGGGGUCAGUGAGACCUCAUUGUGGCCACAUUACAGCCCAGUGCCUCUCCCUGACAAGCCUGUACCCAGCCGGCUCAGCCCACAGCACUGUCCUAUGAACCUUCCUGCACGCCAUUCUCCACCUCAGUAUCUGCUUUCGGGGAACCCAACCUGCGACAGUGCUUCUGUGUGUUUUCAGUCCUGCAGGUUUGAACUCUGACUUUGGAGACUUUUCCAGUUAUCUCGUGGAAUGACAGAUUGUGCCUGUAUGAUAUCAGGCACAAUUAAUGCAAAUUAGGCAGACCUAUUUAUUCUAGAUGUGAAUUUGCUAUUUAUUUUAAAUGUUGAUUUUAUGUGUUAUGUGACUCUGAACUUAUUGCCAAAUAAAAGUUUGAAUUGUA